ACGCCAGCUCCCGGCCGCGGCACAGCAGCCCCGGCGCUCCCCGCGCCGCCCCGCGCAGGCGCCCCCGCCCCGCCGUCGCCGCCGCCGCAGCCAGGAGCCGCUGCACCAUGCCCCGCAUAGAUGCGGACCUCAAGCUCGACUUCAAGGAUGUCCUGCUCCGACCUAAGCGGAGCAGCCUCAAGAGCCGAGCCGAGGUGGAUCUUGAACGCACCUUCACGUUUCGAAAUUCAAAGCAGACCUACUCAGGGAUUCCCAUCAUCGUGGCCAACAUGGACACUGUGGGCACGUUUGAGAUGGCAGCCGUGAUGUCACAGCACUCCAUGUUUACAGCAAUUCAUAAGCAUUACUCCCUGGAUGACUGGAAGCUCUUUGCCACAAAUCACCCAGAAUGCCUGCAGAAUGUAGCCGUGAGUUCAGGCAGUGGGCAGAAUGAUCUGGAAAAGAUGACCAGCAUCCUGGAAGCUGUGCCACAGGUUAAGUUUAUUUGCCUGGAUGUGGCCAAUGGGUAUUCAGAACAUUUUGUGGAAUUCGUGAAACUUGUCCGUGCCAAAUUUCCUGAACACACCAUUAUGGCAGGGAACGUGGUGACAGGAGAAAUGGUAGAAGAGCUUAUUCUUUCCGGAGCAGAUAUCAUCAAAGUGGGAGUUGGACCAGGUUCUGUGUGCACCACCCGCACCAAGACGGGAGUGGGGUACCCCCAGCUGAGUGCCGUCAUUGAGUGUGCCGACUCUGCCCAUGGCCUGAAGGGCCACAUCAUCUCUGAUGGAGGCUGUACGUGUCCAGGGGAUGUCGCCAAAGCCUUUGGAGCUGGAGCAGAUUUUGUCAUGCUGGGAGGAAUGUUUUCGGGUCAUACGGAGUGUGCUGGAGAAGUGUUUGAGAGGAACGGACGGAAGCUCAAGCUCUUCUACGGGAUGAGCUCUGACACCGCCAUGAACAAGCACGCAGGAGGAGUUGCUGAGUACAGAGCCUCUGAGGGUAAGACUGUGGAAGUUCCUUACAAAGGAGAUGUGGAAAACACUAUCCUGGAUAUUCUCGGGGGACUGAGGUCCACGUGCACCUACGUGGGGGCCGCCAAACUCAAGGAGCUCAGCAGGAGGGCAACAUUCAUCCGGGUGACCCAGCAGCACAACACCGUGUUCAGCUAACCCUGGGGACAAAGCAGCGUCUGGCUCGAGUGGAAGCGUCCAAACCUGCUUUUCCCAUCUCCCCCCAAGUCUGUUCCGUCAGAGCUUCUGGCUGCUCCUGAAUGGUGGAAUGCUGUGUCCUCUCUUCUGUCUCCUGCUGCCUGGAGGCUUCGGGGCUCUCCCGCCUGCCUUCUCGGGGCCCAGACGCAAGGCACCGAUUGGGCCAACAUCAGAGCCCUGCUGCCCAGAACUCAUAACCUCAUUGUUCAAACCAACACUUGCACCUUUCUCUUUUUCUCUUUCUCUCUCCCUUUCUUUGUUUUUCUUUCUUUUUUAAAAGAAGAUGGUUUCACUUUAAUAUAAUGCUAUUAUCUUAAGACUUAA